GCAGUGUGCUUUUUCUUUCUAGUCAGGGAUAAAGGGUUAAAAGUGCUCCUGGUGUCGGGGGGUAGAUAUGGAGAGUCGGAAGGGGAGUUGUAUCACAAAAGCUGGUCUGAGGCUAAAGGAAUCUGGCAAGAUGGUCGGGGUGAACAAAGAGGAAAGAACUCACACGGAGCAAGAGGCGGUUGCAAACACUUGUAGCCAGCAGUGAUGGAAAAGCCAAAGAAGAAAACCAAGUGUCAGCUUUUAGAAAGACGGGAUUAAUGAAAAGCACAAGAAUUUUAAAGACUAAAAGAGAUACCGAUUCUCUCUUUGCCAAAGAGCCAGAGUCAGUUCUUUUCUUCUUGGUCCCUGUGAUCCCGCCAUACCUCGUAUCAAAUAAAUAGUGCCAAAAGUGGGUCAAAGAAUGUUAGAGCUGGAAAGGAACCCAGCGAUGAUGCCAUUCUUUUAUUGUACAAAUGAGGAAACUGAGGCCCAGAUAGGUGGAGUAAGUGGCCUGCUCAGGUGACACGGCUGUUUGUUGAGUAUCCAGGGAUUGAAACUUCAAGGACUCUGAGAUUCGUGCUCUUCCCAAAGCAUCGUGCAGUAUACAGAUCUUUGCCUAGAUACAAUUCCAUACAUUUUCUCUGCAGUGUCCUCAGGGAAUGCCCUUUGAAAGGGCCAGCGUGACACUGAAUAUCAUACUUGGGCUUAUGUCAUUUUUUUCAGUCUUCAAGUGGUGUUUAUGGUCUGCUUGGAUCUUAGGUUUCCAAAGCUGUUGGAUAGCCGCCUGGGCCAUAAUAAGCUUUCAGCUGUUGGGUCUACAUUAUUUCAAAUAAUUUUGUUAUCUUUCAAUUAAGGUAAUAGAACUGUGCCUCUCUCCCCAACAUUCUAUUGUUGUCCAUUUGCUUAUGUUAUAUUGCGUUAUGUUCAUUGCCUGUGAGUUCCUAGGUGAGGAUGUAUUUUAUUGAGUGUGCCUUUCAUGUUUUAAAAUUUCAUUUUGUAACACUGUAAAUAUUGGAGUGGUUCUGAUCACUUCAAAUGGGGAGAAUCUUAUUGAUUGAUUUUAUUUUAAGGCUUUGGGUUGUUUUGUUUAUUCAUUUGGGUACCAGUUUCCAUCUCAUGGAAGAUCACAGUUGUUAGAAUGGACAUGGCUAAAUAAGAGAAGGGGCUGCUGAUUUUAAGAAAAACUUCCUAUGUGACAAUUUGUGGUAUCUGUUACGUUUAAUUCAAACAAGUCCACACCUUGGGUCAGGUAAGCGCGUUAUCUAGGAGAUGACUUGUUUGCUACUGUAGCCUCUGGAAGAUGAAAUUUCAAGCUCCAGAUUGAGACACAGGGAAGGAAUGGAGAGGUUUUUUUUUUUUUUUUUUUUUUUUUUGUAAAGCAAACCAUCAGAAAAAAAAAGUUGAUUUCUAUCACCAGUAGUUUGGUUAUUGCAUAACUUGAAGCUAAACUCUGCACAAAAUAAUCUUUGCUAUAUACCCAACUAGGUAAACUAUCCCACCUUCUCAUCAGUUCUCACCUUUUCGGUGCUUGUAUUUUUUGCCCACGGGAUAUUAAUAUGGAUUGUGUUCAGAAAUUUAAGGUGUGUACUUCAUAGUAUGUAUGAUUGUAGGAGAAAAAUGUGCUAUCAUCGUUUGGAGUGUUACAACAUAAAUAUUUUGGUCAACACUUCCUAUCCUGCUCUGACUUUUCAUCUCAUCUCCAUUUUCUUCCUCUCUUGAUUGUUUUUAUGUCAUUUACAUAUGUAAAAGCCACAUCAAGACUAAAGUUGCCAUUUAUUACUUUUUGAUACUUAAGUCGAGUUUUUUCAAAUCAUAGUAUUGUUAGUAUUCAAAUUGUCUGUAAUUUUUGUUAGGCUUAUAUAUUAUGAAUCCAUUUGUUGUGGUUUAUUUGGCUUGUUGUUAUGUAGGUAGGUGACACAGGUAGUCUUAUUGUAAAAGGAAGACGUUAUAGAUAGGUAAAUAACAUGCUCAAGAUUAGAUGCAGGUUACAGGUGGAAUCGAAGGAAGCCUAACUAUUUUCGUGCCCUACAAAAAUGUCUGUAUCUCAUAAAGUUAUUCACAGAUUUCUGGACAUUCUAUCUGUGACACAUUUUUUCCCUUUCUGUUAAGAGUGCAGAUUACUGCAUUAUUCCUACAAAAGGAAGCAAAAUAACCCUAGUUUGUAUGAUUUUUCUGAUAAUUUGAAACUUAUUCGUUUAAAAAGCUAUCUGGCAAUUCCAGGUUACUGGACUCUUGAGAAGAAUAUCCUUUUAUUUUGAUACUAUAAAAUAUCAAAGUAUCAAAAUACUUUAACUGUGCAACUUAAUAAAAAUAAUGCUUCAAAGUUAGCUCUGCACUAUCGCUGUCCUCAAAUGUGUGGUAUUUAAAGGAAGAAAAUGUUUUUAAUUCUGAGCUUUGUGAAUAGAACUCUUCUAAAAUCAGAAGUUUUUUUUUUUCUCCUGCAGUGUUGGAAACACAACAGUUUUAUGCUUAUUUCUGGGAAUAAGAAAGUCAAACUUAACAAUCUAGUUUCCAUUGAUCAGACAGUUUUUGUACUUAAAUUUAAGUUCUAAGCAUCAGAGUGAUAAAUACUUUUUAAAAUUGUAUUCACUGUUAAUUAUAGUGGCCUUAUUUGAAGUAAAAUCUUGACAUUGGGUGUUUUAUUAAUGAUGAUCCUCUGCUACUGAAAAGCCUAUGUCAGUUUGGAGAAGAUUUUGCACAUCUAAAUCUAUGCUGUUUUUACUAAUCAAAAGAGAAGAGCAAUUUACAGGUGUUAGAUUUUUAGUUGGUUGAAUGAGACCCUCACUUUUGAUGGUUUCAGAGUUGAAGUGACGUUUUAUUACUUUUGUUAGUUUGGGUCACACCCAUCACUUCCUUGGAAGGUAUCUUUGAGGUUUGGUUUCCUUUUUUUUUAAAUGGUAAUAUUGGGGUGGGGGUGCUUCCUGUUUGUAUUUUCAAAAUUAGGUCCACAUGUUAACCUUCUUGUAGUGUCACAUUUUUAUUUUAAACUUAUACAGACAAACAUCAGAUGCCAUGUGGUUUGUCUCUGACCCUUUGCGCUACUUCAUGACAGCUUUACUGAGUGAAGCCUGAAUACCCAAUCGGGAAGGCAAGAUGUUCUUGUCUUUUCCCAACUCUCUUCAAAGUUUAACAGCCUUGGAAGGAGUCUUAGAACAGCAACAAAAGCACAAUUUACAGAAAAAUGGAGGUGCUGCUAUCUGUUUCCUCGCAGGUACUUGGAAAAUGUAUAGCACUAAGAUAGAGUUGAAACAUGUUAUGUAGAGCCUUGAAUGUCGGUGCUUCAAAGAGGAGUUGCUCUGGGUUUACAUGAUACAGAACCCCAUGGUUUAUAUUAAGUAGUAAUGAUAGCCGUUUUUCUGGACUCGCUUAAAAGCCAUACACAGUGUCAUGGAAAAGAGUUAAGAACAAGGUGAAAUUCAGGGUAUGGUAUUAGAGCUCAGGAGGAAUCACCUUCAGCCUUAAAACUCUUCCUUUACUCUCCUGGAUCACUUAAGUGAUAGGUCACUUUUAAUAUAAAUGUUGCAGGAUGAGUUAAGUGGAGCCUUGAGAAAUAUGUGUAGAUUGUUUCAGUGAUUAAAGCAAGUGUUCUUUUCCUGGCCUUUAACUCGCUUUAUGCUAAGAAGUGUAAUAACUAAAUAGACUCCUAAUUGAAUUGACAUUCAGAUGUGUUUGCAGUUUAGGGGGAGUUUACCUCUUCUAAAUUUUCAUUUGGAUCCCAUUACUAAAAGCAGUAUUGCAUUAGCAUGGUGCACAAUUAUGUACAAUUCAAUUUGCAAAUGAAGUUAAUACUUGGAGUAUCUUGACUUCCUAUUCCCCUGCUGCCCCAAUAUUCAAGAAAGGAGAAGUUAUAAUUUGUCACAUACAAGAUGGUUUCUUCUUUAGGUUUAUUCUUAAUAACUAUGUCCAUUUUCACAUGGAUGACACCACUGAGAUGAUGAAUACCUGUAUUGAUUGAUUGAUGAAGAACAUUUAUCUUUUUCUACCUACUUUUGGAAGCUAGCUUGCAAAAUCUACUGCAACAUUCACUCUUCAUGUAUCCUUCUAUUACCUUUGGUACCCUGAAUAACCUUUUAAAAAUUUUUGUACUUUUCUAAUAUGAAGAGAAGUAGCUUCAUAUUCUAUGCUAGUUUUCUGAGGUGCUUGUGCUGACUCAUUUUUUAAAUUAUACUAAGAUAUAGAGCAUGGUUUGAGAGCAGUAAUGAGAUUCUCAGAAAAUAUGAAAACUUUCCUUUCUGACUAGUUAGAGAAAGGUUGGGGAAGACAAGGGGAAAUACAUCAAUGAGCCAAUCAAUUAUUGUUAUUUGUUGGGAUUAAUUUGGUGACUAAUAUUUUUAAUGCCCAUCAGGCUACUAAAUGUGAAUUUGGCUUUACCCUGUAAUGAUAACAGGACAAACCCAACGGGUUUCUAACAUUGCUUGUUUUCCCCUGGUAGGGGAUUUCUUUGCAUAUGGGAAAUCAGGCCGAAGUUGCCAGUAACAGCCACAUCCAUGAUUUGUAUUAAAAAUAACUAUUCAUCAUUCUGGGCUAGAGCUCUGCUUACCAUGGCUCACCUGGGAAGAUAUUCUGAUUAUGUAUCUAAUCAUUAUGAUGCCACCUUUCGAGAGGUGAGCAGACAAUUAACAAGUCCUUCAAAUUAUGUUCAAAACCCAGAGUUUGAGAAAAUGUUCCAACGCCUUCAAGUGUGAAGAUAAUAAAAACAUUACCUAAUGCUUACCGUUCACUGACAGUGUGCUGGGCAGACAUUGUUUUCAGCUCUGGCCUUGUGUUAACUCGUGAUUCUCAGAGGAGUGGGUAUUAUUCCCAGAUGGAAGAUGAAGAAAUGGCCACAGAGAAGUUAAGUAAUUUGUCCAAGGUCACAUUACUGUUCUUGGCGGGGCUGAUUCCAGAGACUGCAUCCCUAACUAGUGUACAGCAAAAGCGAGCUGGCCACUGCCACUUUGUUAUAAGACAUUUUGUUUCUUUGAGGCUUGUAUUUCUUUGUGUUCCCAAAUGGAGUCUCGUUGGUUUUUGAAUAGAAAAUAUUUUUAUAUGUUUAGGAUUUUUUUAAAUGUUGAUGAAGAUGGUGAUAAAUAUUUUUCCAAUUAAAGUAUAUACUUCUGGUGGAAAUUAUAUUAAAGAAGAGAAAGUCUUAAUUUUUAUUAUAAGUUGUCUUUCAUUCUUCUUCCCCUAGCAUUACCGUGUACAUCAUAGAAGAAGAGCUAUAAGCUGUCUCCUUGGCCUCUGUUUACAAACAAAGGGAUCAUUUGUGCCAAUGUAGUGGGUUUGUGUUGACAUGCACGUCUGUACUGAGAACUCAACAAUCCCACUCAUUUUAUUUACAACUUUAUUUUGCGGGGAUUUCUGUCCUAUUCUUGUUGCAUUAAAGCUUUUUAGAGCAUUAGUCAUGAUUUCUGAGACAGAUUUAAGAAUUUUACUUAUUUGGGCUAAUUUAUUAUUAUUAUUUCUUGAGACAGAGCCUCGCUCUGUCACCCAGGCUGGAAUGCAGUGGCGCGAUCUUGGCUCACUGCAACCUCCGUCUCCUGGGUUCAAGAGAUUCUCCUGCCCAGCCUCCGGAGUAGCUAGGACUACAGGCAUGUGCCACCAUGCCCAGCUAAUUUUUGUAUUUUUAGUAGAGACGGGGUUUUGACAUGUUGGCCAGGCUGGUCUCGAACUCCUGACCUCAGGUGAUCCUCCUGCCUUGGCCUUCCGAAGUGCUGGGAUUACAGGCAUAAGCCACCAUGCCCAGCCUAUUUGGGCGAAUUUUUAAGGCAACUGAACUAUUGUAUGUCUAGAGCUCUGCAAAGGCCAUUAGAAAAUAGUCUCAGAUUUUUUUUUUUUUUUCAUUUAUGAUGCUUACUUUCUCUCAGCACUUUUCCUUGGGAGUGGAUUGUGAAGUUAAGUCUUGGAAACAGAAUUCACAACCCUAAAGCGUAGUGCUUUAACUUUGGGAGAUCAAGUCACAGACAAGAAGAACUUCAAUUCCCUGUGCAGAGUAUAAACUUGUUCAAAUAAACAGAGGAUGUUAGCUUCCAGGAUUGUCAACUGUCACCUUUGACCAGGGUUGAAUUUUCUUUGAAUGUUGACAGAAGUUACAAUGUCAGUGGAAAAAGCUUAAUGUGAGGUAUCUAUAACUCAGAAUUUCCUUAUGUUUGUGUCAGUGAGAUCCUACAAUUAAAGCUGCUUCUUUUUUUCUAUGUCUGAUGAGUUUUAAAAGCCUUCACUGGGGUUUUCCAGCCUUUAGGUGAGAGUAAGUUAAAAAGUUUGUGAGAAACUAUUUUUUGUUGUCUAAAAUUCAGAGCCUAGGUCGGGCCCAGUGGCUCACGCCUGUAAUCCUAACAAUUUGGGAGGCCGAGGCAAGCGGAUCACGUGAGGUCAGGAGUUGGAGACCAGCCUGGCCAACAUGGUGAAACCCUGUCUCUACUAAAAAUACAAAAAUUAGCCAGGUGUGGUGGUGCACGCCUGUAAUCCCAGCUACUCAGGAGGCUGAGGCAGAAGAAUCACUUGAACCCAGGAGGCAGAGGUUACAGUGAGCCGAGAUCGCACUACUGUGCUCCAGCCUGGGAGACGGAGCGAGACUCCAUCUCAAAAAAAUAAAUAAAUUAAAUAAAUUCAGAGCCUAUAGCUGGUGGCAAGUCACUGUUUUUGAAGGAGUGGGAUUUUAAAAAAUCUAACCUGGGCUAAAUGUUAAGUUACAUUCAUACAUGUCAUUGUAGCCUAUAUAAAAAGAAACUUGAACACUUGAUCUCUUAAAGUACUAAAAAUUGGAAUUCAUCAGCUUUGUAAUAUAGCAUUCAUUCUACAGUAUAUUUAAAUAGGUAAAAUGUUCUGUUAGAAAUAAUGCUAAUUCUGUUUUUUUGUUUAAUGUUUCUAAAAAUCUUUUGGUCAUCUUUUAGGUUUAGGAAAAGUAGCAAAUUAGAGAUCUACAGAAAUCUACAGCUCUUUAAAAAUGAAACAGUUCACCCUGUGAAUUUGUUUGCAGGAUUGGUGAUCUGUUUCUGAUGCCAGGAAGGUGGGACUCCUAUCUCAUUUCUGAUAGAAAGUGAGGGAAAGCUAUGUAUAGUGAGAACUGGAUACUAGAUUCUUAUUCCGAAGGCAUGGAAGGUUUAAUAUGUAAGGAUACAAUGUAAAUAGUCCCUCUUUUUGUAUUUUUCUUUGGUUAUUGUUACGUAACUAUAGUCGUUUGUCACUUAAUGAUACAUGGUGACAAAGUUCUAAGAAAUGCAUUAGGCGAUUUUGUCAUUGUGGUACCAUCAUAGAGGGUACUUACACAAACGUAGAUGGUGAGCCCUACUGCACACCUAGGCUGUAUGAUAAAGCCUAUUGCUCCUAGACUACAAACCUGUGGAACAUGUAUACUGUAUUGAGUACUGUAGACAAUUGUAACACAAGGAUUGUAAACCAUGGCUGUGUGGAUACAAGCUCAGCAGCUCCAAGGAGAAGCCCUUCAUCAGAUGCAAGCGUUAUAUGGCCAGCAUUUUCCCAUUGAGGUGCGGCAUUAUUUAUCCCAGUGGAUUGAAAGCCAAGCAUGGGACUCAGUAGAUCUUGAUAAUCCACAGGAGAACAUUAAGGCCACCCAGCUCCUGGAGGGCCUGGUGCAGGAGCUGCAGAAGAAGGCAGAGCACCAGGUGGGGGAAGAUGGGUUUUUACUGAAGAUCAAGCUGGGGCACUAUGCCACACAGCUCCAGAACACGUAUGACCGCUGCCCCAUGGAGCUGGUCCGCUGCAUCCGCCAUAUAUUGUACAAUGAACAGAGGUUGGUCCGAGAAGCCAACAAUGGUAGCUCUCCAGCUGGAAGCCUUGCUGAUGCCAUGUCCCAGAAACACCUCCAGAUCAACCAGACGUUUGAGGAGCUGCGACUGGUCACGCAGGACACAGAGAAUGAGUUAAAAAAGCUGCAGCAGACUCAGGAGUACUUCAUCAUCCAGUACCAGGAGAGCCUGAGGAUCCAAGCUCAGUUUGGCCCGCUGGCCCAGCUGAGCCCCCAGGAGCGUCUGAGCCGGGAGACGGCCCUCCAGCAGAAGCAGGUGUCUCUGGAGGCCUGGUUGCAGCGUGAGGCACAGACACUGCAGCAGUACCGCGUGGAGCUGGCCGAGAAGCACCAGAAGACCCUGCAGCUGCUGCGGAAGCAGCAGACCAUCAUCCUGGAUGACGAGCUGAUCCAGUGGAAGCGGCGGCAGCAGCUGGCCGGGAACGGCGGGCCCCCCGAGGGCAGCCUGGACGUGCUACAGUCCUGGUGUGAGAAGUUGGCCGAGAUCAUCUGGCAGAACCGGCAGCAGAUCCGCAGGGCUGAGCACCUCUGCCAGCAGCUGCCCAUCCCCGGCCCAGUGGAGGAGAUGCUGGCCGAGGUCAACGCCACCAUCACGGACAUUAUCUCAGCCCUGGUGACCAGCACGUUCAUCAUUGAGAAGCAGCCUCCUCAGGUCCUGAAGACCCAGACCAAGUUUGCAGCCACUGUGCGCCUGCUGGUGGGCGGGAAGCUGAACGUGCACAUGAACCCCCCCCAGGUGAAGGCCACCAUCAUCAGUGAGCAGCAGGCCAAGUCUCUGCUCAAGAACGAGAACACCCGCAAUGAUUACAGUGGCGAGAUCUUGAACAACUGCUGCGUCAUGGAGUACCACCAAGCCACAGGCACCCUUAGUGCCCACUUCAGGAAUAUGUCCCUGAAACGAAUUAAGAGGUCAGACCGUCGUGGGGCAGAGUCGGUGACAGAAGAAAAAUUUACAAUCCUGUUUGAAUCCCAGUUCAGUGUUGGUGGAAAUGAGCUGGUUUUUCAAGUCAAGACCCUGUCCCUGCCAGUGGUGGUGAUCGUUCAUGGCAGCCAGGACAACAAUGCGACGGCCACUGUUCUCUGGGACAAUGCUUUUGCAGAGCCUGGCAGGGUGCCAUUUGCCGUGCCUGACAAAGUGCUGUGGCCACAGCUGUGUGAGGCGCUCAACAUGAAAUUCAAGGCCGAAGUGCAGAGCAACCGGGGCCUGACCAAGGAGAACCUCGUGUUCCUGGCGCAGAAACUGUUCAACAACAGCAGCAGCCACCUGGAGGACUACAGUGGCCUGUCUGUGUCCUGGUCCCAGUUCAACAGGGAGAAUUUACCAGGACGGAAUUACACUUUCUGGCAAUGGUUUGACGGUGUGAUGGAAGUGUUAAAAAAACAUCUCAAGCCUCAUUGGAAUGAUGGGGCCAUUUUGGGGUUUGUAAACAAGCAACAGGCCCAUGACCUACUCAUUAACAAGCCAGAUGGGACCUUCCUCCUGAGAUUCAGUGACUCAGAAAUUGGCGGCAUCACCAUUGCUUGGAAGUUUGAUUCUCAGGAAAGAAUGUUUUGGAAUCUGAUGCCUUUUACCACCAGAGACUUCUCCAUUCGGUCCCUAGCCGACCGCUUGGGAGACUUGAAUUACCUUAUCUACGUGUUUCCUGAUCGGCCAAAAGAUGAAGUAUACUCCAAAUACUACACACCAGUUCCCUGCGAGUCUGCUACUGCUAAAGCUGUUGAUGGAUACGUGAAGCCACAGAUCAAGCAAGUGGUCCCUGAGUUUGUGAACGCAUCUGCAGAUGCCGGGGGCGGCAGCGCCACGUACAUGGACCAGGCCCCCUCCCCAGCUGUGUGUCCCCAGGCUCACUAUAACAUGUACCCACAGAACCCUGACUCAGUCCUUGACACCGAUGGGGACUUCGAUCUGGAGGACACAAUGGACGUAGCGCGGCGUGUGGAGGAGCUCCUGGGCCGGCCAAUGGACAGUCAGUGGAUCCCGCACGCACAAUCGUGACCCCGCGACCUCUCCAUCUUCAGCUUCUUCAUCUUCACCAGAGGAAUCACUCUUGUGGAUGUUUUAAUUCCAUGAAUCGCUUCUCUUUUGAAACAAUACUCAUAAUGUGAAGUGUUAAUACUAGUUGUGACCUUAGUGUUUCUGUGCAUGGUGGCACCAGCGAAGGGAGUGCGAGUAUGUGUUUGUGUGUGUGUGUGUGUGUGUGUGUGUGUGCGUGUUUGCACGUUAUGGUGUUUCUCCCUCUCACUGUCUGAGAGUUUAGUUGUAGCAGAGGGGCCACAGACAGAAGCUGUGGUGGUUUUUACUUUGUGCAAAAAGGCAGUGAGUUUCGUGAAGCCUGGAAGUUGGCCAUGUGUCUUAAGAGUGGCUGGACUUUGACAUGUGGCUGUUUGAAUAAGAGAAGGACAAAGGGAGGAGAAAGCACAUGUGCUCCAGUGAGUCUUCGUCACUCUGUCUGCCAAGCAAUUGAUAUAUAACCGUGAUUGUCUCUGCUUUUCUUCUGAAAUGUAGAUAACUGCUUUUUGACAAAGAGAGCCUUCCCUCUCCCCCACCCCUGUGUUCUUGGGUAGGAAUGGGAAAAGGGGCAACCUACAAAGAUUGUUGGGGCAAGGGAAGUCACAAGCUUUCGGAUGGGCGGUGGCUUUUCACAAAACAUUUAGCUCAUCUUAUUCUCUCUUUGUCCUCUCUCCCCUCCUGCCCGCCCGCACCCUGGAAUUGCCACUCAGUUCCUCUGGGUGUGCACAUAUGUUUGGAGAAAUAGAGGAGAGAAAAGAGGGCCACGUAACUGAGAGCUUACAGUGCCAAUGCCGUUUGUGUUCUGGCCAGAGUGGAGUGCGCAGCCCUGACUCCCAGGCGCUGAGAUUGUUGCCUGGUUACCCAGGAAGCUGCUGUUCCGGCUGCCCAGCCUUUCUCUGAGCCAGCGGAUGCACAGUCCGUGGCCUUCUUCAGGCUUAUUGAUGAUGCUUUUUGCAAAUGUUGAAUCAUGGUUCUGUUUCUAAGUUGGAUCUUUUUUGUUUUCUCCUUGCCACCCUAAUUUGACAUCAAAAUUCUCUCUUGUGCAUUGGGCCCUGGGUCAUUCAAACCCAGGUCACCUCAUUCCCCUUCUCUGUUCACACCUAAUGUCUUGAAGAGUAGGUAGCAGCAGUGUGGGCUGAACCUAGGCCAGCUUGCUUAGCGGGUCACCCUGCUGUGAAGUCCUGGCAGGUGUUGGUAAUGUGUGGAAAUGCAGUCAGCAAGUUUGCUGGGGAGUUUGAUAAAAGUAUAAAACAAAACAAAAAAAGCCUCGGUAUAAUUUUGUUCCACGACUUCUUCUGUAGCUUUACACCAGAAGGAAGGAAUGGGCUACAGCAGGUAGUGGAGGAAGAGGGGGGUGAGCAGGUGUAUUAAAAUAGCUUACGGGUAAGGCCUAAAAGGUCACCCCUCGGCCCCCUCUCCAAAAGAAGGGCAUGGGCACCCCCAGGAGAGGAUGGCCCCAAAAACCUUAUUUUUAUACAUGAGAGUAAAUAAACAUAUUUUUUUUACAAAAAUAACUUCUGAAUUUAUCAGUGUUUUGCCGUUAAAAAUAUUCCUCUAUAGUAAAUUAUUUAUUGGAAGAUGACUUUUUUAAAGCUGCCGUUUGCCUUGGCUUGGUUUCAUACACUGAUUUAUUUUUCUAUGCCAGGCAGUAGAGUCUCUCUGCCUCUGAGGAGCAGGCUACCCGCAUCCCACUCAGCCCCUCCCUACCCCUCAAGAUUUGAUGAAAAUUCCAACCAUGAGGAUGGGUGCAUCGGGGAAGGGUGAGAAGGAGAGCCUGCCUGCUCAGGGAUCCAGGCUCGUAGAGUCACUCCCUGCCCGUCUCCCAGAGAUGCUUCACCAGCACCUGCCUCUGAGACCUCGCUCUCUGUUCCAGCAACCCUGGUUGGGGGGUCAGACUUGAUACACUUUCAGGUUGGGAGUGGACCCACCCCAGGGCCUGCUGAGGACAGAGCAGCCAGGCCGUCCUGGCUCACUUUGCAGUUGGCACUGGGUUGGGGAGGAAGAGAGCUGAUGAGUGUGGCUUCCCUGAGCUGGGGUUUCCCUGCUUGUCCAGUUGUGAGCUGUCCUCGGUGUUACCGAGGCUGUGCCUAGAGAGUGGAGAUUUUUGAUGAAAGGUGUGCUCGCUCUCUGCGUUCUAUCUUCUCUCUCCUCCUUGUUCCUGCAAACCACAAGAUAAAGGUAGUGGUGUGUCUCGACCCCAUCAGCCUCUCACCCACUCCCAGACACACACAAGUCCUCAAAAGUUUCAGCUCCGUGUGUGAGAUGUGCAGGUUUUUUCUAGGGGGUAGGGGGAGACUAAAAUCGAAUAUAACUUAAAAUGAAAGUAUACUUUUUAUAAUUUUUCUUUUUAAAACUUGGUGAAAUUAUUUCAGAUACAUAUUUUAGUGUCAAGGCAGAUUAGUUAUUUAGCCACCAAAAAAAAGUAUUGUGUACAAUUUGGGGCCUCAAAUUUGACUCUGCCUCAAAAAAAAGAAAUAUAUCCUAUGCAGAGUUACAGUCACAAAGUUGUGUAUUUUAUGUUACAAUAAAGCCUUCCUCUGAAGGGA